AGUUCCUUAAUCAUUUCACGGUGCCUUCGGACGCUUUUUUUCCACCUAAAACGUUUAGUUUCAGCUCAGUGAUCAGCUACCCCAGCUCGGCGGGGGAGCGGAAGGCUUGAAUUAUUCCGACCUGUGAGCGGCCCCUGGCACCAAAAAAAAAAAAAAAAAAAAAAAAAAAAGAAAAAAAAAGGCACAAAAAAGUGGAAACUUUUCCCUGUCCAUUCCAUCAAGUCCUGAAAAAUCAAAAUGGAUUUAGAGAAAAAUUAUCCGACUCCUCGGACCAGCAGGACAGGACAUGGAGGAGUGAAUCAGCUUGGGGGGGUUUUUGUGAAUGGACGGCCACUCCCGGAUGUAGUCCGCCAGAGGAUAGUGGAACUUGCUCAUCAAGGUGUCAGGCCCUGCGACAUCUCCAGGCAGCUUCGGGUCAGCCAUGGUUGUGUCAGCAAAAUUCUUGGCAGGUAUUAUGAGACAGGAAGCAUCAAGCCUGGGGUAAUUGGAGGAUCCAAACCAAAGGUCGCCACACCCAAAGUGGUGGAAAAAAUCGCUGAAUAUAAACGCCAAAAUCCCACCAUGUUUGCCUGGGAGAUCAGGGACCGGCUGCUGGCAGAGCGGGUGUGUGACAAUGACACCGUGCCUAGCGUCAGUUCCAUCAACAGGAUCAUCCGGACAAAAGUACAGCAGCCACCCAACCAACCAGUCCCAGCUUCCAGUCACAGCAUAGUGUCCACUGGCUCCGUGACGCAGGUGUCCUCGGUGAGCACGGAUUCGGCCGGCUCGUCGUACUCCAUCAGCGGCAUCCUGGGCAUCACGUCCCCCAGCGCCGACACCAACAAGCGCAAGAGAGACGAAGGUAUUCAGGAGUCUCCGGUGCCGAACGGCCACUCGCUUCCGGGCAGAGACUUCCUCCGGAAGCAGAUGCGGGGAGACUUGUUCACACAGCAGCAGCUGGAGGUGCUGGACCGCGUGUUUGAGAGGCAGCACUACUCAGACAUCUUCACCACCACAGAGCCCAUCAAGCCCGAGCAGACCACAGAGUAUUCAGCCAUGGCCUCGCUGGCUGGUGGGCUGGACGACAUGAAGGCCAAUCUGGCCAGCCCCACCCCUGCUGACAUCGGGAGCAGUGUGCCAGGCCCGCAGUCCUACCCCAUUGUGACAGGCCGUGACUUGGCGAGCACGACCCUCCCCGGGUACCCUCCACACGUCCCCCCCGCUGGACAGGGCAGCUACUCAGCACCGACGCUGACAGGGAUGGUGCCUGGGAGUGAGUUUUCCGGGAGUCCCUACAGCCACCCUCAGUAUUCCUCGUACAACGACUCCUGGAGGUUCCCCAACCCGGGGCUGCUUGGCUCCCCCUACUAUUAUAGCGCUGCCGCCCGAGGAGCCGCCCCACCUGCAGCCGCCACUGCCUAUGACCGUCACUGACCCUUGGAGCCAGGCGGGCACCAAACACUGAUGGCACCUAUUGAGGGUGACAGCCACCCAGCCCUCCUGAAGAUAGCCAGAGAGCCCAUGAGACCGUCCCCCAGCAUCCCCCACUUGCCUGAAGCUCCCCUCUUCCUCUCUUCCUCCAGGGACUCUGGGGCCCUUUGGUGGGGCCGUUGGACUUCUGGAUGCUUGUCUAUUUCUAAAAGCCAAUCUAUGAGCUUCUCCCGAUGGCCACUGGGUCUCUGCAAACCAAUAGACUGUCCUGCAAAUAACCGCAGCCCCAGCCCAGCCUGCCUGUCCUCCAGCUGUCUGACUAUCCAUCCAUCAUAACCACCCCAGCCUGGGAAGGAGAGCUUGCUUUUGUUGCUUCAGCAGCACCCAUGUAAAUACCUUCUUGCUUUUCUGUGGGCCUGAAGGUCCGACUGAGAAGACUGCUCCACCCAUGAUGCAUCUCGCACUCUUGGUGCAUCACCGGACAUCUUAGACCUAUGGCAGAGCAUCCUCUCUGCCCUGGGUGACCCUGGCAGGUGCGCUCAGAGCUGUCCUCAAGAUGGAGGAUGCUGCCCUUGGGCCCCAGCCUCCUGCUCAUCCCUCCUUCUUUAGUAUCUUUACGAGGAGUCUCACUGGGCUGGUUGUGCUGCAGGCUCCCCCUGAGGCCCCUCUCCAAGAGGAGCACACUUUGGGGAGAUGUCCUGGUUUCCUGCCUCCAUUUCUCUGGGACCGAUGCAGUAUCAGCAGCUCUUUUCCAGAUCAAAGAACUCAAAGAAAACUGUCUGGGAGAUUCCUCAGCUACUUUUCCGAAGCAGAAUGUCAUCCGAGGUAUUGAUUACAUUGUGGACUUUGAAUGUGAGGGCUGGAUGGGACGCAGGAGAUCAUCUGAUCCCAGCCAAGGAGGGGCCUGAGGCUCUCCCUACUCCCUCAGCCCCUGGAACGGUGUUUUCUGAGGCAUGCCCAGGUUCAGGUCACUUCGGACACCUGCCAUGGACACUUCACCCACCCUCCAGGACCCCAGCAAGUGGAUUCUGGGCAAGCCUGUUCCGGUGAUGUAGACAAUAAUUAACACAGAGGACUUUCCCCCACACCCAGAUCACAAACAGCCUACAGCCAGAACUUCUGAGCAUCCUCUCGGGGCAGACCCUCCCCGUCCUCGUGGAGCUUAGCAGGCAGCUGGGCAUGGAGGUGCUGGGGCUGGGGCAGAUGCCUAAUUUCGCACAAUGCAUGCCCACCUGUUGAUCUAAGGGGCCGCGAUGGUCAGGGCCACGGCCAAGGGCCACGGGAACUUGGAGAGGGAGCUUGGAGAACUCACUGUGGGCUAGGGUGGUCAGAGGAAGCCAGCAGGGAAGAUCUGGGGGACAGAGGAAGGCCUCCUGAGGGAGGGGCAGGAGAGCAGUGAGGAGCUGCUGUGUGACCUGGGAGUGAUUUUGACAUGGGGGUGCCAGGUGCCAUCAUCUCUUUACCUGGGGCCUUAAUUCCUUGCAUAGUCUCUCUUGUCAAGUCAGAACAGCCAGGUAGAGCCCUUGUCCAAACCUGGGCUGAAUGACAGUGAUGAGAGGGGGCUUGGCCUUCUUAGGUGACAAUGUCCCCCAUAUCUGUAUGUCACCAGGAUGGCAGAGAGCCAGGGCAGAGAGAGACUGGACUUGGGAUCAGCAGGCCAGGCAGGUCUUGUCCUGGUCCUGGCCACAUGUCUUUGCUGUGGGACCUCAGACAAAACCCUGCACCUCUUUGAGCCUUGGCUGCCUUGGUGCAGCAGGGUCAUCUGUAGGGCCACCCCACAGCUCUUUCCUUCCCCUCCUCUCUCCAGGGAGCCGGGGCUGUGAGAGGAUCAUCUGGGGCAGGCCCUCCACUUCCAAGCAAGCAGAUGGGGGUGGGCACCUGAGGCCCAAUAAUAUUUGGACCAAGUGGGAAACAAGAACACUCGGAGGGGCGGGAAUCAGAAGAGCCUGGAAAAAGACCUAGCCCAACUUCCCUUGUGGGAAACUGAGGCCCAGCUUGGGGAAGGCCAGGACCAUGCAGGGAGAAAAAGCAGACUUCCUCUGGCCACCGCUAAGUAUUUUGUUCCCUAAGUCCCCCACAGGGUGGUGGAACAGAAGAGAAAACUAAGGCUCAGCAAGGUGGAGUCCUCAAGCAGUGACUGGUGGGGGUGGGGCUGGGACUCGGGCUCCUGACCCCCAACCCAUGGUGUUCCCUGUCACCCUGGUCUAUCCACAUCUCCUAUUCCUGAGGAGAGUUGACAGUAAGAGCAGUGAGAGAUGGUUCUGGGCCCCAUGCCCUAGACAAUCAGUCUGUAAGAACUGCCAAGGAAGCCUGGUCACCCAGGCCAGGGAUGGAGCCCAGCGAGCUCACAGCAGGCACAUGCACCCCCGCCCCCACCCAGAACCUGCGGGGCAAAGAAGGGAGGUAGUUGGGGCCAGAGUCCACCUCCAGGAGCCAGGGUGAGCUGGCUGCAGCUUCCACCUGUCAGGUAAGGUAGGAGAAGGUAUGUUACCUGGCAUCUCUCUCCCUGCCUCCCUCCAUUUAGCAGGAAGUGGUGGGGUCAGGGGUCUUCAGCACAGACUUCUUGAGCCUCUGCCCCCUGUCACCCUUCUUUUGGAAUGAUGUGUACCCACAUCUUUGGAUCCUGCCCUCCUUGUGGUUCCAGGCUGUUGGGAGGAGGUCAGCCUCCCCUGAACCAGCUGCCUGAGGCAUGCAGCAUCCUUCCUCGGCAAAGCCCACCUGGCUCACAGCGGCCCCCUCUCCCCAUCCUGUUCCUCUUCUUGCCCUGUAAUGAGCUCCCCCCAUACCUUUCCUCCCUCACCUGAGGCUUUGCUGGUCCUCAGAUUGGUUUUGUAUUUGUGAGACAACCACUUGACUCCUGGGCUGCCAGGCGGAAGCACAAGCGCACAUGGAUGCACACGGAUGUUCUCACACACACACGCCCGCUCUCACCAAUUCACAGCACCUCGUGGUCCAGCGGAGCUGCCUGGGAGCUUGGUGAGGAUGGCUCCAAAGGACACAAGCCGUUGAGUAGAUGCCAGAGAAUUCUGAAUGGAAAACACAAGUCCGGGGCCUCACCAGCAUCGUGGCAGAAGGCCUGGGGCAUUUCUCCAUGGGCCUUCUUCCCUGUGUUCGAGCUCUGACUUUUGGAAAAGGACAUUGUGGAUUUUAUGAAAAUUUCUCAUACCAUCAGUCUAGCUCCAACCUAGAAAAAUUGGAUGAUAUAUCAAACCCAACAUCCCUUUCCCAAGGCACCUUAGUUAAGGCUAGCCCUUCCAUAACUGACAUUGUACGGUGCUUUGCAAUCCUCAACCACUCUGUGGAGCAAAGAGCAUGAUGCCUACUUUAUAGACGGGGAAAUUGACAUUUGGGGCUCUCACGGCAACAUAGAGGCGAAGUGAAUUCUCAGAUCUCCAGGCCCCAUUCUCUCUCCACCGAGUUGUGCUCCUGUCAUGGGAGUGUAUGGCUUAAAGACACUCCCCCACCCCCAUUCCCUAGAAAUCCCCCAGACCCACAAUCAGGCAAGAAAGAACAGGGACCCAGAGGCUGGCCUGACCUAGGGGCCUGCAGGUUGGCGGCUUUGUUUCCUAAGAACAUUGAAACCUGCGGAGUCUUUGACCAAAUCCACAACAGUGCUUCUGAGGUUUCAUCCAGACUCUUUCCCAGCUGUCCCUGAGGUUCAGAGGGUAUCAGAGUCAAUUCAAGGCCAUGCCAUAAUCCCUGACCAGGCCUGGACAUGGGUCCAGCCCUGACUCCAGGGGUCCAGGUGCCAAGGUCAUGUGCUGUCCCCCACUUCCCUUUCUUUGCCUUCGCACUUUGGAACAGGCUCCAGGCCUGGCUGUGACAGUAUGCAGGAGUGCCCAAGCCAGGGCCACCAGGGUGUCCACAGCCCCUGGAAACACAGAUCACAAUCUCAAGUCCCCUGAAUGAACUGCUUCCUGGGUGAACGGGGUGGUGUAGCCUUGCCACUCGGGCAGCGCACCAGACAGUACGGUGCAGCAGUGCCCGAGAUGCCCAGAAGUGUGCCUGCCCCCCUGAGUGGCAUUCAAGUAUGAAAACUUGUAAAAUUUUCUGUCGGCCUAAAGAAAAAUGUCCAUGGGCCAAACUUGACCCACUGGGCACCAGCCUGUGAGCCCCAAUGCCUGUCAAUUGCCCCCUUUCUCAUUCACCUCCUGUCCUUUGUUGCAGAUUUGGAGGAGAUGGGAGCCCAGAGAGGUGAGAGAUGUGCUUCAGGGUGUCCAGCAAGGCAGGGGUAGAAACGGGCACGCCCAGAGCCUGCCACUCUCCCAGGCCUCAUCUUGGGCUCUUGCAAGUCUUGCGCUUUGAAGAUGGAGUUGGGUGGAAGGUCAGAGGCGCUGGGGACGGGAUUGGGGAGCUGCUGGGUUUUCAGGGGAGGUCAGUGCUGCUUGGGCACCUUUCACAUGUGCAGGGAAGAGACUCAGAUGUGGCCACAGGGCACUGAGGGGUGAAAUCCAUUUACCAGAAGUCACGCUCCAGAACGACUGCCCAGCCUUGGCAGCCAGUGGCUCCAGCCACCCCCUCCUCAUGACAUUCAGCCAGAAUUGAGCUCCAAGCCAGGGAAGCAAAUCUUAAAAACCAACCAAGCACCCUGACACAGCCCUAGAAACACGAUGAGUCUGAAAUACAGCUUCCCAGGAGGGGAGUCUAAGAUACAGCUUCCCGGGAGGGUGGAAACCAACUCCUGCCCCACGGCCAGGCCAGGCCCAGGCAGGCAUGGGUGGAUCCCACAGGGCUCUGAGCUAGACCGGCUCCACGGUGGCCCCACUACGAGGCCAGUUCUGCAGUCUUGGCCUUGUCACCCAUCGAGAGGCUGCUCUGAUGGUUCCCAGCCACACACCAGCUCUCCUGGGGAAACUAUUUCUUUCGUUCUUUUGGCCUCGGAGAGGUCCGAGGCAAGUACAUUUCUUAAAAGGUAAUAAAAUGCAUUAUUGGAAAGUUGGACAGUCAGGCCACGACUCCUAGCCCACGGCGUGCCCCACCUCCCAGCAGCCCCUUCAGCCCCUUGCCCCUGUUGCCCCAAACCUCAGGGUUCCCUCUUGCAUAUUCAUGGGGGAACCACAGUGCUGAUGUGUACUUCCCCACUGUCAGCUCGGCUGCACCUCGUGUGGCGCCAGGUCCCAAGGGCCUCUGCAGAGGCCAGGCUGUGAGCCCCUUGCCUGCCUGCUCCCCUGAUGAGGCAACAGCUUCUCUGAAAUGAGCUGCCGGCCAGGAGCAGGCAGGCACCAGCCUGUCUUUCCUUUUCUGGUAAUUCCUCAGCACUGAGGCUCCGUUCCUGGGCACCCCAGGAUUGAAGGGAACCUCAGAAUCAUGUCACUGCCAUUCUAGAGUUUCAAUCCAAGGGGUCCCCUUUAGCUCAUCUCCAAGAUGGGUAAACGUAGCCACCAUUCAGAAAGCCCAGAAAUUCUUGUUCCCACAUCUUAGACCCCUGAGCAACACAAGGAGAAAAUGCAGCUGCUUACCUAUUAAUAUCUACUGAGGGACAAUCAGCAAAGCCUCAAAGGAGUCGUCUCAGGUAGGGUACUUGGCCUGUGGCAGGAGAGACAGAGGCACAAACCCACCCACCCAUCAGCUUCCGGUGGCUGAUCGGGGCCCAGGGAGGGAAGCAGGUGAAACAGCAGGGUGGGGGUGACUUGGCAGUCGUGCAUCUCCUCCCCGACUCUGAGGCCUGGCAGGAGGAGGCCACACCAGCCUCACCUGCCCUGACCCCCGCCCCCCACCCUGUGACCCUGUGGCUAUGGCCGCUGGUCGCCCUUGUCCCCAAAAUCACCAUGCCUGUGGCCACGUCCCUCAUCUUCUCCAAAAGCAUCAUUAAGAACAAGUGAUUUUGGAUGAUGGAUUUUUGAUUUACAAACGGCGCAUUUCCCUUGGAGUGGAACAGAAAGGAAACCAUUUAAUGGCGCCCUUCUUUUCAAGCAUGAAUACAUUUUAAUGAAACUAUUUUAUUGUAUUUGAGGAAAUGGAGAGUUGAACAUUCCAACCAAUCAAUAGCCAAUUAAUUGCUAUAAAGCUAAAAAGAAAAUAAAUAAAUCCUGAGUCUAUUUUAAACACUGCAAAAAGUUCAGAGCCUCAGAAUCUGGCCUUCCCCUCCAUAAGGUGCACGAGCAUGUAAACACACACACACACACACACACACACACACACACACUCACUCACUCCCCUACACCUCAGACAUACUUGAAACUCAGAAACAGCACUGAGUCUCCCCAUGCCAAUUCUUGCCUGCUGUCUUCGACUUGGGUCAGAGAAGGUGAGCAGACCCGGCAGCAGCCUGUCCCGGGGCUCAGGAAGAGGCAGGCCCAUCCCCUGGCCCCAAGCACCCAGCACAACAGAGGGUGGCGGGCAGUGAGGGCCUGGCGUUGCCUGGGCCCCACUUCUCAGCCCCAGCUGCUGGGCCUCCAAGGUUGGGCUGAGGAUGGAGUUUUGGCUCUGGGUUUGCCCUGACUCCUGCUGGAAGACGCUGCCCUGGUUUUUCACCCUCUAGUGGCCUUGGACAUUGAGUAUUUGUAGAAAUGCAGAUUACAUUGCAAAUGGAAACCUUUGCCAGGAAGACACAUGCAUUUUGCUUUUAAUUCUUUGAGACAUUUGAUUUUGUCUUAGGGACUGACCUUUCAGCAUCAAAGAAAUACAUAUCUACUGUAUCCGCCAAAGUUUGUGAUGCCUGCAUAGACGCUUACUUGUAAAAAAAAAAAAAUACAAAAAAAUACAAAAAAACCAACAACAAAAACCACAAUUGAAUUGCCUUUGAAAGUGGGAGAUGAUCUGUCUCCAACGGAUUGAAAAAAAAAAAUGCUUCUUAAAAAAUGUGUAUGUUUUGUAUUCUUUUUUUCUAGUAGAAAAUAACUGACUUGAAAUAUUGGUGGUUUUUUUCUUAGUGACGUGUGUUGCUUUUGUGUGUAAUAAUAUUUGAAUGUAAUUACAGCAGUGCCAAUUUGCCAAAGAUGUUGGACAUAUUUUUCUUUUUUGGGGAGGAGGGCAGGGCUAGGGGUGGGACUUGGGAGAAAACAGGGGUGGGGUUUUGGUUUAAUUUUUUUUUUACUUUUUUUUCCUUGUCAAACCUGAAAUUUGUGGCUUCCUUUUAAGUUAAAUGGUUGACUGCAACACCUUUAUUUUAGAUUAGUUGGAGAAACAUGCAAUAAGAUUGGCGUAGUUUCAAUAUCUGUGUGUCUUUUCAUGAGUGGCUGUUACUUGUGAAGAAUUGAUUUUAUGUAACCUUUAUGUGAGAUAAUUAUUUGUAAAUAUUUGCCAUAAUUUUAUUGGUUCCUAAAAUAAAAGUAAUUUUUUAAGUUCAGAAAAA